AGAAUUGUUAAAAUCUUUGUGAAGCACACCACUGAAGAUGAGGUUGAAAAACCUGACUUUUAUCAUCAUAUUGAUAAUCUCAGGAGAACUCUAUGCAGAAGAGAAACCCUGUGGUUUUCCUCAUGUGGAAAAUGGAAGAAUUGCCCAAUAUUACUAUACUUUUAAAAGCUUUUACUUUCCAAUGAGCAUAGACAAAAAAUUGUCAUUUUUCUGCUUGGCUGGUUAUACCACUGAAAGUGGAAGACAAGAAGAGCAAACCACGUGUACAACAGAAGGCUGGUCUCCAGAGCCAAGGUGCUUCAAAAAAUGCACUAAGCCUGACCUGAGUAAUGGUUACAUCUCUGAUGUAAAGUUAUUGUAUAAAAUUCAAGAGAACAUGCGUUAUGGUUGCGCUUCAGGGUACAAAACCACUGGAGGGAAGGAUGAAGAAGUGGUUCAAUGUCUCUCUGAUGGAUGGUCUUCUCAACCAACCUGUAGGAAAGAACAUGAAACAUGUUUGGCUCCUGAAUUAUAUAAUGGAAAUUAUUCCACAACACAGAAAACAUUCAAAGUGAAGGACAAAGUACAAUACGAAUGUGCUACUGGCUACUACACAGCUGGAGGAAAGAAGACAGAGGAGGUAGAAUGUCUCACAUACGGAUGGUCUCUCACACCAAAAUGUACCAAAUUAAAGUGCUCUUCUUUAAGAUUAAUUGAAAAUGGUUAUUUUCAUCCUGUAAAGCAAACCUAUGAAGAAGGAGAUGUCGUUCAGUUUUUCUGUCAUGAAAAUUAUUAUCUAAGUGGAUCUGAUUUAAUUCAAUGCUAUAACUUUGGUUGGUACCCAGAAUCUCCUGUAUGCGAAGGAAGAAGAAACAGAUGUCCUCCUCCACCUCUGCCCAUAAACUCCAAAAUUCAAACACAUUCAACAACUUAUCGUCAUGGAGAAAUAGUUCAUAUAGAAUGUGAACUUAAUUUUGAGAUCCAUGGGUCAGCAGAAAUACGUUGUGAAGAUGGAAAAUGGACAGAACCUCCAAAAUGCAUUGAAGGACAGGAGAAGGUAGCCUGUGAGGAACCACCCUUCAUUGAAAAUGGUGCAGCAAAUUUACACUCUAAGAUUUAUUACAAUGGGGAUAAAGUGACAUAUGCAUGUAAAAGCGGCUACCUUCUCCAUGGAUCGAAUGAGAUAACUUGUAAUCGUGGAAAAUGGACACUUCCUCCUGAGUGUGUUGAAAAUAAUGAGAAUUGUAAGCAUCCUCCUGUUGUAAUGAAUGGGGCUGUUGCAGACGGGAUAUUGGCAAGCUAUGCAACAGGAUCCUCAGUGGAAUAUAGAUGCAAUGAAUAUUACUUACUGAGGGGAUCAAAAAUAUCUCGUUGCGAACAAGGAAAAUGGUCAUCCCCACCUGUUUGCUUGGAACCAUGUACUGUUAAUGUGGAUUACAUGAACAGAAAUAACAUAGAAAUGAAGUGGAAAUAUGAAGGGAAAGUCUUACAUGGAGAUUUAAUAGAUUUUGUAUGUAAACAGGGAUAUGACUUAUCUCCAUUAACCCCAUUGUCUGAAUUAUCUGUGCAGUGCAACAGAGGAGAAGUGAAAUAUCCUUUAUGUACUAGAAAAGAAUCUAAAGGAAUGUGCACAUCUCCUCCUCUUAUUAAACAUGGAGUCAUUAUUAGUUCAACAGUAGACACCUAUGAAAAUGGCUCUUCAGUAGAAUACAGAUGUUUUGAUCACCAUUUCCUAGAAGGAUCUAGGGAGGCCUAUUGUUUAGAUGGAAUGUGGACUACACCACCAUUGUGUUUAGAUUGCCCUGGCCAGAACUUCCAACACUAUGUUGAAUAGGAGUGGUGAGAGAGGGCAUCCCUGUCUUGUGCCAGUUUUCAAAGCAAAUGCUUCCACUUUUUGCCCAUUCAGUAAGAUAUUGGUGGUGGGUUUGUCAUGAACAGCUCAUAUUAUUUUGAGGUACAUUCCCUCAAUACCUUGUUUAUUGAGAGUUUUUAGCAUGAAGGGCUGUUGAAUUUUGUCGAAGGCUUUUUCUGAAUCUAUUGAGAUAAUCAUGUGGUUUUUGUCAUUGGUCCUGUUUAUGUCAUGGAUUAUGUUUAUUGAUUUGUGUAUGUUGAACCAGCAUUGCAUCCCAGGGAUGAAGCCAUCUUGAUCGUGGUGGAUAAGCUUUUUGAUGUGCUGCUGGAUUUGGUUUGCCAGUAUUUUAUUGAGGAUUUUCACAUCGAUGUUCAUCAGGAAUAUUGGUCUAAAUUCUGUUUUUUGUUGUUGUUGUGUCUCUGCCAGGCUUUGAUAUCAGGAUGAUGCUGACUUCAUUAAAUGAAUUAGGGAGGAUUCCCUCUUUUUCUAUUGAUUGGAAUAGUUUCAGAAGGAAUGGUACCAGCUCCUCUUUGUACCUUUGGUAGAAUUCGGCUGUGAAUCCAUCUGGUCCUGGGCUUUUUUUGAUUUGUAGGCUAUUAAUUAUUGCCUCAAUUUCAGACCCUGUUAUUGGUCUAUUCAGACAUUCAACUUCUUUCUGGUUUAGUCUUGGAAGGGUGUAUGUGUCCAGGAAUUUGUCCAUUUCUUCUAGAUUUUCUAGUUUAUUUGCAUAGAGUGUUUAUAGUAUUCUCUGAUGGUAGUUUGUAUUUCUGUGGGAUUGGUGGUGAUAUUCCCUUUAUUAUAUUUUAUUGCAUCUAUUUGAUUCUUCUCUCUUUUCUUCUUUAUUAGUCUUGCUCUCAGUCUAUGUAGUUUGUUUAUCUUUUUUAAAAAAACAGUUCCUGGAUUCAUUGAUUUUUUUGAAGGGAUUUUUUGUGUCUCUAUUUCCUUCAGUUCUGCUCUGAUCUUAGUUAUUUCUUGCCUUCUGCUAGCGUUUGAAUGUGUUUGCUCUUGCUUCUCUAGUUCUUUCAUUGUGAUGUUAGGGUGUCGAUUUUAGAUCUUUCCUGCAUUCUCUUGUGGGCAUUUAGUGCUAUAAAUUUCCCACUACACACUGCUUUAAAUGUGUCCCAGAGAUUCUGGUACGUAGUGUCUUUGUCCUUACUGGGUUCAAAGAACAUCUUUAUUUCUGCCUUCAUUUCGUUAUUUAUCUAGUAGUCAUUCAGGAGUAGGCUGUUCAGUUUCCAUGUAGUUGUGCAGUUUUGAGUGAGUUUCUUAAUCCUGAGUUCUAAUUUGAUUGCACUGUGGUCUGAGAGACAGUUUGUUGUGAUUUCUGUUCUUUUUCAUUUGCCAAAGAGUGUUUUACUUGCAGUUAUGUGGUCAAUUUUGGAAUAAGUGCAGUGUGGUGCUGAGAAGAAUGUAUAUUCUUUUGAUUUGGAGUGGAGAGUUAUGCAGAUGUCCAUUAGGUCUGCUUGGUCCAGAGCUGAGUUCAAGUCCUGGAUAUUCUUAUUUACCUUCUGUCUCGUUGAUCUGUCUAGUAUUGACAGUGGGGUGUUAAAGUCUCCCAUUAUUAUUGUGUGGGAGUCUAAAUCUCUUUGCAGGUCUCUAAGGACUUGCUUUAUUAACCUGGGUGCUCCUGAAUUGGGUGCAUAUAUAUUUAGAAUAGUUAGUUCUUCUUGUUGAAUUGAUCCCUUUACCAUUAUGUAAUGGCCUUCUUUGUCUCUUUUGAUCUUUGUUGGUUUAAAGUCUGUUUUAUCAGAGACUAGGAUUGUAACCCCUGCUCAGCAAUAGUAGACGACCCUCCCCCCAUAACGCUGUCGUGUCACAGGUUGAUCUCAGACUGCUGAGCUAGCAGUGAGCAAGGCUCCAUGGGCGUGGAAACUGCUGAGCCAGGCAAGGGAGGGUAUCUCCUGGUCUGUCGGUGGCUAAGACCUUGGGAAAAGCACAGUAUUUGGUCAGGAGUGUACCAUUUCUCACUGUGCUGCCCAGGCUGGAGUUCCUUAGAAACAAAUCAGAAACAAAUCUCUCCCUCUCUCUCUUUCUCUCUCUCUCUCUAUAUAUAUAUAAAUAUAUAUAUAUAUGAGUUAGUUCCAAGAUGGCCGAAUAGGAACAGCUCCGGUCUGCAGCUCCCAGGGAGAUCAGUGCAACACAAUGAGACUCUCUUUGUACAUUUUGUUCUUCAAGUUAGUAGCAUUCCUUGAACCUUGAUGUACUUGAUAUCCUUCAUGGGUUUUAGAAAUGUUUGGCUAAUAUCUUUUAAAAUGUACAUUUCUCACCUCUUCUGUGAUGCCAUAUUACAUAUAUUACAUCUUUUUGCUAUGCCAUUGUCUCUUUAAAUCUAUAUUUUCUCUCAUUUUCUUCUUGUUUCACUGUAGUAAUUUUUUGGUAAUUUUCUCAUUGUAUCAUUUCUUUGUUUCUAUUUGGUAAUUUUCUUCUAGUUUAACAAUCCUCUCUUUAGAUGUAUCCAAUCUGCUUUAAACUCAUCUUUUGAGUUCUCAAUUUCAGUUAUCAUCUUUGCAUUUCUAUUUUAUAUUUUCUUUUUGUAGAUUUGAGUUAUCUGAUGAAAGAUCCUAGCUUAACAUCAACUUCUUGAACAUAUAAUUCAUACUUUUUAUUAAGGCUUGUCUGCAAACUCCAAUAUCUGGAUCUAUUUUUUAGCCCCAAAUUCUUGAUAUUUUUGUUAACAGUUGAUUGAAUUCCAAAUAUUAUACGUGGAAAAUUUCAGGAUGUUUGGAUGAUGUCAGCUUACUCCAAAGAAGACUCAUCUCAUCCUCUGGCUGAUGAUUAGUGUAGAGGCAGUUGGUUUUAAUACAAUUAGAAAUAAAGCUUUCUCUAUGUUUGUUUUCAGACCUCUGUUUGCCUUUUCUCACAGACUGUAACUCUCCAGGGCUCUUUACAGAGGGUUUGUUGUGUGUAUUAAAGCUUUUUCUCCUUGACUGUCUCUGAUAUUACUGGGAGACUGCCAAAUGCCCACUGUAACUUUUUAUUUACUUUCUGCUUGGCUUCUCAUCCUAUGCCUCUAUACAAGUCAAGGAUAAGCAGUACCUUAGGGAAAAGCUAGUGCAGAGCCUCAAACUCAUAUCUCUACACUUCCUAUCCUUCUAAAUUCUUUAUUCUUCAAGUCCUGGCUGCUUUGGUUUACCGAAAUUCUCAUUUUUCUAUCUUCAACUCCAUGAGAUUUUCAGAAGUUCUGCUGGCUGUAUGCCUAAGCUUACCAUUCUCUAUCAUCUAACCUCUCAGGUCAGACUUAGAGUCAACAAACACCUCAAGAGAAAAAAAUGGCACAUAGAAUUUUUUUUUUUUUUUAGACAGUCUCCUUUUGUUGCCCAGGCUGGAGUGCAGUGGUGCGAUCCCUGCUCACUGCAACCUCCACCUUCUAGGUUCAAGAGAUUCUUCUGCCUCAGCUUUCCCGAGUAGCUGGGAUUACAGGUGCAUGCCACCAUGCCCGGCUAUUUUUUUUUUUUUUUUGUAGAGAUGGGGUUUCACCAUGUUGGCCAGGCUGGUCUCAAACUCCUGACCUCAGAUGAUCCGCCCGCCUUGGCCUCCCAAAGUGCUGGGAUUACAGGUGUGAGUCACCACGCCCAGCCUCACAUAGAUGUUGAACUCACCUGAAUACAUUUUUUCCAGAACCUUACUUCCUUGACUAAGUUCCUUGGAGGUUUUCUGAUACCUCGAAAUGCUUCCUGUUUUUCAGAUUUUCUGGUUCUUAAUAGAAGUGCUGGUUUGAUAUAAUCUCCUCUGUCAUAGCUGAAAGUUAAAGGUCCAUGAAUCAACUUUUAAAUUUAUUUUAAUUUAAAUCUCAUGUUCUGUAGAACAGUGACAUCGUAAAUUAUAGUGCUAUUCGACUUCAUUUUCACAACUAUUUUGUAAUGAGUGUAAUAAUUCUUGUUCAUUUUCAUCACCUGUAGCACUUCCAGCAUAAUGUUUGACACAUAGGCAUUUAAUAAGUAGUUGUUGAAGAAAGUAACUGAACACAGUGCUCUCAGCUGCGGUUUCACUUUCUGUGGUUUCAGUUACCUGCUAUAAACUGCAGUCUGAAAACGUUAAAUUGAAAAUUUCAGAAAUAAACAACUUAUAAAUUUUAAAUUAUGCACUUAGUAGUAUAAUAAAAUUUCAUGCCAUUCCAUCCUUCCUGCCCCAGAUAUGCUAAAAAGAAGCUGUAAAGUGCUUCCUUUAAGUGAAAGGGCGGAAAUUCUUAACUUAAAAAGAAAGGAAAAAUAAAUGUAUGCUGAGGUUGCUAAGAUCCAUGGUAACAAUGAGUCUUCUGUCUAUGAAAGUGUGAAGAAGGAAAAAGAAAUCCAUGCUAGUUUCGUUGUUGCACCUCAAACUGCAAAAGUUACAAGCCACAGUGUAUAAUAAAUGUUUAGUUGAGGUGGAAGAGGCAUUAAAUUUGUGGGCAGAAGACAUGAACAGAAACAUGUUCCAAAAGAAUGACAACAGGGUUUAGCAUUAUCUGCGGUUUCAGGCAUGCACUGGGGCUCUUGAAAUGUAUCCCCUGUAGGCAAUCAGGGAGGGGCAUACUGUAAGUAAGUUUGUUAAUGUACUACAGGUAUAUGAUUGAUAUGCCAUAUUAGCAACUCUGGACCUUUUUACCUGUCUCAGAAGUUAUUCCUUAAUGCUAGGUCAUCCAGGAGACAAAUAAGGACAUAAGAAAUCCCAUUUUCUGAAAUAAUUUGAUAUUUGAUAUUUUAGAAAUAUUAAUGUUUUUAUUCUGUAAAAAAAAUCGAAGAGGUUUUUUUGUGUAUUUUAAUACAUACUUUACCAUUCUCUUUGGUUUACGAUACAUGGGAAAGGACACAACUAUACUUUGUAUGCUUAGAAUUUAAAACGUCUUAAUCCAGUCUUGAUAUUUCUUAACUAGAAAUUUGAAAGAGAAGUAACUGUCAACCAUUUUGGAUGGCAUGAGGUUAUAAAGCUUGGGUCAGUGUUGAGAAUCUACAUUUCCAUAAAAUGUUAUUUAUACAGCAAUUAAUAAUUUGUCUCAUGAGAAUUUUAUUUGAACUUUCUGAAGAAGGAAAAGGGAAAAGAGCAUGAUAUCAAUGACCAUUAGUAACUGUCAAUGCUUCCCCCCAAAUACCUUUUUGUUUGUUUGCUAUCUUUGAAAAAGCUAAUGACAUAAAACUAAAAUACCUUUUAGUUUUUAAAACUGGAAGAAAAUACCUUUUCUCCAAAUCCAGGACCACAGAGAGAAAUGGCUCACUGUUUUCUGUGAGAUUUGAACAUAUUUUCUGACUCAAAUAUUAAUUCUGAUUAACUGACUUGCUGCUCUUAGGCCUGAGAAUUUUAAGGUCCUCAUGAGUAGGCAACACAACGAUUCCUGUUCUUACCAAGAUGUAACAAGAUAGUUUUCUUCUUUUUCUUUCUUUUUUUUUAAAUUGUUGUUCCCAGAGCCAUGCACAUUAUCUUUUACUGAAAUGGAAAAGAAUAAUUUACUUCUGAAAUGGGAUUUUGACAAUAGACCACACAUUUUGCAUGGUGAAUAUAUUGAGUUUAUUUGUAGAGGAGAUACUUAUCCAGCUGAAUUAUAUAUUACUGGAUCUAUACUUAGAAUGCAAUGUGACAGAGGGCAGUUAAAAUAUCCAAGAUGUAUUCCAAGACAAAG